GGAACUGCGCCUAGGAGGCCGAGGGAGGAGGCGCUCCGCAGACCCUGGCGCGCCGCGGAGAAGCUCAAACUUUGGCAGGGUAAGGAUUUUUAGGGGCUCUUGAGCUGGAAUUUUUUGGGGGGCGCCGGGAGGUGUGCUGGGGCCGCAGACCCCAUACAGGAGCAAUCAUCUGGGGGGCUAAAUGUGACAAACCGAGAAGAUGGCCAAGAUCAACACCCAAUACUCCCACCCCUCCAGGACCCACCUCAAGGUAAAGACCUCAGACCGAGAUCUCAAUCGCGCUGAAAAUGGCCUCAGCAGAGCCCACUCGUCAAGUGAGGAGACAUCGUCAGUGCUGCAGCCGGGGAUCGCCAUGGAGACCAGAGGACUGGCUGACUCCGGGCAGGGCUCCUUCACCGGCCAGGGGAUCGCCAGGUUUGGAAGAAUUCAGAAAAAAAGCCAACCGGAGAAGGUGGUAAGAGCAGCCAGCCGUGGGAGACCUUUGAUUGGGUGGACACAGUGGUGUGCUGAGGAUGGUGGUGAUGAGUCUGAAAUGGCUCUGGCAGGGUCUCCCGGGUGCUCGUCUGGACCCCAGGGCAGGCUGUCGCGCCUCAUCUUCUUGCUGCGCAGGUGGGCUGCCAGGCAUGUGCACCACCAGGACCAGGGACCGGACUCUUUUCCUGAUCGUUUCCGUGGAGCCGAGCUUAAGGAGGUGUCCAGCCAAGAAAGCAAUGCCCAGGCAAAUGUGGGCAGCCAGGAGCCAGCAGACAGAGGGAGAAGCGCCUGGCCCCUGGCCAAAUGCAACACUAACACCAGCAACAACACGGAGGAGGAGAAGAAGACGAAAAAGAAGGAUGCGAUCGUGGUGGACCCGUCCAGCAACCUGUACUACCGCUGGCUGACCGCCAUCGCCCUGCCUGUCUUCUAUAACUGGUAUCUGCUUAUUUGCAGGGCCUGUUUCGAUGAGCUGCAGUCCGAGUACCUGAUGCUGUGGCUGGUCCUGGACUACUCGGCAGAUGUCCUGUAUGUCUUGGAUGUGCUUGUACGAGCUCGGACAGGUUUUCUCGAGCAAGGCUUAAUGGUCAGUGAUACCAACAGGCUGUGGCAGCAUUACAAGACGACCACGCAGUUCAAGCUGGAUGUGUUGUCCCUGGUCCCCACCGACCUGGCUUACUUAAAGGUGGGCACAAACUACCCAGAAGUGAGGUUCAACCGCCUACUGAAGUUUUCCCGGCUCUUUGAAUUCUUUGACCGCACAGAGACAAGGACCAACUACCCCAAUAUGUUCAGGAUUGGGAACUUGGUCUUGUACAUUCUCAUCAUCAUCCACUGGAAUGCCUGCAUCUACUUUGCCAUUUCCAAGUUCAUUGGUUUUGGGACAGACUCCUGGGUCUACCCAAACAUCUCAAUCCCAGAGCAUGGGCGCCUCUCCAGGAAGUACAUUUACAGUCUCUACUGGUCCACCUUGACCCUUACCACCAUUGGUGAGACCCCACCCCCCGUGAAAGAUGAGGAGUAUCUCUUUGUGGUCGUAGACUUCUUGGUGGGUGUUCUGAUUUUUGCCACCAUUGUGGGCAAUGUGGGCUCCAUGAUCUCGAAUAUGAAUGCCUCACGGGCAGAGUUCCAGGCCAAGAUUGAUUCCAUCAAGCAGUACAUGCAGUUCCGCAAGGUCACCAAGGACUUGGAGACGCGGGUUAUCCGGUGGUUUGACUACCUGUGGGCCAACAAGAAGACGGUGGAUGAGAAGGAGGUGCUCAAGAGCCUCCCAGACAAGCUGAAGGCUGAGAUCGCCAUCAACGUGCACCUGGACACGCUGAAGAAGGUUCGCAUCUUCCAGGACUGUGAGGCAGGGCUGCUGGUGGAGCUGGUGCUGAAGCUGCGACCCACUGUGUUCAGCCCUGGGGAUUAUAUCUGCAAGAAGGGAGAUAUUGGGAAGGAGAUGUACAUCAUCAACGAGGGCAAGCUGGCCGUGGUGGCUGAUGAUGGGGUCACCCAGUUCGUGGUCCUCAGCGAUGGCAGCUACUUCGGGGAGAUCAGCAUUCUGAACAUCAAGGGGAGCAAGUCGGGGAACCGCAGGACGGCCAACAUCCGCAGCAUUGGCUACUCAGACCUGUUCUGCCUCUCAAAGGACGAUCUCAUGGAGGCCCUCACCGAGUACCCCGAAGCCAAGAAGGCCCUGGAGGAGAAAGGACGGCAGAUCCUGAUGAAAGACAACCUGAUCGAUGAGGAGCUGGCCAGGGCGGGCGCGGACCCCAAGGACCUUGAGGAGAAAGUGGAGCAGCUGGGGUCCUCCCUGGACACCCUGCAGACCAGGUUUGCACGCCUCCUGGCUGAGUACAACGCCACCCAGAUGAAGAUGAAGCAGCGUCUCAGCCAACUGGAAAGCCAGGUGAAGGGUGGUGGGGACAAGCCCCUGGCUGAUGGGGAAGUUCCCGGGGAUGCUACAAAAACAGAGGACAAACAACAGUGAAAAUGCAGCAUCUGUCUCCUGCUUCACAGGGUCGACUGUCAGGGUGACCGUAUGUGGCCGCAGCUGUGUGGCAUGGAACUUGGUCAGGGUUGAAUUCCAGCUCUACUCACCCUUUGAAAGCUGUGUGACUGCCUGAGAGAACCUGUUUCUUCACCUAAAAAAUGGGACUUUUUGUCUCAGUCCCAGUGAAGUGCCAGGUUUGAUUGUGAAGUCCGCAUGAAACACUGCACCAGGCAGGGCUUUGCAAAGUGCAAGGUAUCCCCAGUCCAAGUAUAUGAAAACGUGCACACAGGACUCUCAUUACUUUUUUAUGGAAUCUGCAAGGUGUUUUUAGGCUUUUUAAUCUGAUUUUCUUAUAAAUGAAAGAUUAUUUAGUCACCUUUCUCCUGUCCAACUUCACCACCACCUGAUAAUGGGUAUAUAACAGGAAGCUGAAGGUACAACAUAGUGACUAAAAUUCAGACUUACACAAGACAGUUUGAGGCAUAUUUCUUAAUCUGGUAUCACCUCGUGUGUUCUUUGGGGCCCUAGAAACCCUGGCUUUUGGGAGUGCUAUGGCAAGUAGAAGUUCUGCCGGAUGGAAAGAGGCUGCCCCAUUUGAGGUCAUUUAAAAUCUGUGAAGCAAAUCCAGACUCCUUGCCGUUCAGCCACUGUGAAACCAGAAUCUGCUUCACAGAAAAAAGCAUCUCAGUUAGGAGAAGAGACAUCCCCUCCUUCUCACUUGCCAAAGAGAUUCAAAGACAGCCCCUAUCCUCCAUUCUUGAGUCAGGGCCCUAGGUGACCUAUUCUAACUCAAGGAGGAGAGCUAUGUACAGGGAGAGCAUUUUAGAUUGAAGGUUGGAAUGGUGUACUAAACCAAAAAAGCUGACAACUGAGAGUUUUAGAAGAUUAGACCAUUAGGAACGUAUCUUUGCAAACUGCCCAUUCACCCAUGAAGAGGAAGCCUCAAGAUCCCUUGGAAUUGCAUCCCAAGGCAAAGCUUUUGGCUCACCGAAAGCUCACAGAUUGCAGAAAUUAGCUUUUUUAAAAAACAAACCCCAGUAAAUAUAAUUUCAUUAACAUUUUAUAACAGAUUUAUAUUUUUGAGUUCCGUGAUUGCAAAUUAUGACCUCAAAUUCCAUCCUUCACUUAUGUAACAUGUUGCAAAUUACCCAAAGAUGAGUCUUUCUUCUUUCUUUCCUUUUUCCUUUCUUCUUCCUUUCCUUUUUUCUUUCUUCUUCCUUCUUUCUUCCUUUUUCUCUCUCCUCUUUUCCUCCUCAAAAUGUAUAUAUUUUAAAAGCCUUAACUGUUAGUUAUGCCUGCAUUCAUAUUUGCACAGGAAAAAUAAAGACCUGGAUUUAAAAAUA